GGAGACGUUGGCGGCAGAGGCGGAGGCGGACGGGGUCAGCCCAAAGCAGAGGCUCGGCCAUGAACUUACCCGGGACAGCGGCGGCGGCGGACCUUUUGGCCAUCUUCUCGCAGAGUGCUCCCUGCUAACGGGGACAGAUUUUAACAUUAUGGCAGGGAGGCAUCAGAAUCGUAGUUUUCCUCUUCCAGGAGUUCAGUCAAGUGGUCAAGUACAUGCAUUUGGAAAUUGUUCAGACAGUGAUAUUUUGGAGGAGGAUGCUGAAGUGUAUGAACUUCGAUCCAGAGGAAAAGAGAAAGUCCGAAGAAGUACAUCAAGAGAUAGACUUGACGACAUUAUAGUAUUAACAAAAGAUAUACAAGAAGGAGAUACAUUAAAUGCAAUAGCCCUUCAGUACUGUUGUACGUGUUCCAUUUCUCAAUGAAUGCCAUCGUCCAUCAAGUUGACCAAACCAGAAAUCUAAGCUUCAUACUAGACCCACUUUAUCUCUCUGACAUGAAUCAGGUGAUACAUGAUUAGGUUUUAAAGUAUUGAUGGAAAUGAAUGGGACUAAUAGAUGGUGGGAGAGCCUGGCAUACCAAUUGGUAAUCUGCCAGACACUCCCCUCUUCCCCCAACACAGUGGAAUAGGAUAUACAGACAGGUUAUCUCACAGUGGAUGGGAUAAUACAAACAGGUUGAGGAAUGUAUAAUAUAUAGAGAAAAAGCUUAUAAAAGUGAUUAAUCUUGAAAGUAGUUGAAUAAUGCAUUUACACUGAGAAGUUUGGGAGGGAAAUGGCUUCAGAAAUAAGGGGGAUAAAUUACCAAUUUUUUAAAUUCUAAGGUAUAUAUGCUUUUCCACACAUUUUAGCAUCUUUUUUUGGAAUGGUGGCAUCUUCAAUUUUUGGUGAAGUUUUUUUUUUCCCUAGAUAUACAUAAAAUAAUACUGCAUCUUAGAGUUAUGGCAUCUUAGUUUUGAUAAAAUAUGGUAGUUUUAGUUGGGUAGCAUUUGUCUAUAUUCCAGUUUCCAAACUGGAAUAAAGAACAUAACUACCCAUAAUCCUUCCUUCACAAAUUGUUUACAAGCAGAAGGACUGUGGUAUUUAUGCAUGAUGCACAAAGGGAAGCAGCAAAGGAUUCUAGAAUCUACUUAAAUAGCAUUAAUUAGUGUUACUAACAUAUAUGGGUGAUAGUAAAAAGUAGUUGGUGAUUUCCUAAGAUUGGUACAUCUAAAGUGGUGUAGAAUUCUCAUCUACAAAUAAAAUUAAAAUUUCUCUGGGUGCAACUUAAUACUACUAAUAAUUCAACUUUUUUUUUCCUCCAAAAGUAACUAGAAUGAAUGACUAUUGCUGCCUUUAUUUUGAUUGGAAUUCAGUUGUAUGUUGCUUUUUUUUCCCCCCCACAGGUAGCAGAUAUCAAGAGAGUUAACAAUCUCAUCAGUGAUCAAGACUUUUUUGCCCUUAGGUCUAUCAAAAUUCCAGUAAAAAAGUUCAGUUCCUUGACCGAAACACUUUGUCCUCCAAAAGGAAGACAGACUUCACGUCAUUCAUCUGUUCAAUACUCUUCCGAACAACAGGAAAUUUUGCCAGCUAAUGAUUCUCUUGCUUACAGUGACUCAGCUGGUAGCUUUUUAAAAGAAGUAGACCGAGACAUAGAACAAAUAGUAAAGUGUACAGACAAUAAGAGAGAGAACCUCAAUGAGGUAGUAUCGGCCUUAACAGCACAACAAAUGCGUUUUGAACCUGAUAACAAAAACACUCAACGUAAAGACCCCUAUUAUGGAGCAGACUGGGGAAUAGGGUGGUGGACAGCUGUAGUGAUAAUGUUGAUAGUAGGUAUAAUAACACCAGUGUUUUAUUUGUUGUAUUAUGAAAUUUUAGCUAAGGUGGAUGUUAGUCAUCAUUCAACAGUGGACUCUUCACAUUUACAUUCAAAAAUCACACCCCCAUCACAGCAGAGAGAAAUGGAAAAUGGAAUUGUGCCAACUAAAGGAAUACAUUUCAGCCAACAAGAUGAUCAUAAACUGUAUAGUCAAGAUUCUCAGUCACCUGCUGCUCAACAGGAAACAUAGCAAUUAGCUCAUAAUCAAAUGUUAGUGGUCACAUGUGCAUCUGGAAUGUGGUGAAUCAGUUAUAUCCAAUAAUAGCUUCAAAGGCAGAAUUUAGAGAGAUUGAGGAUGCUUUUGUUUUUAACAAAAGGGUUUCACACUUUGAAAAUUUUUUGAGCAACUAGUUGUUGAUGUUGAGAGCAGUUGAUCCAUAAAUCUGGUGUGUGAAUGUUUCAAGCAGAAAUUAAUUUAAAUGUGUGUUUAGGAAGUACUUAACUUGGAAGAUGUAUCAUUUUUCUUAAAAUGCAUGUUUAAAUUUUAUUUUUUUAAGUAAUUUUUAAAAAGUUUAUUAAUGUUAAAUUUAUGAUGCAGAAUGAUAGCAUCAGAUGUCUGCAGCUGAAAAAAAUUUACUACUAUGAACCCCCAAAAUAUUCAGUUGCAAGAAAAUUUGAUUCUAAAAUUAUUCAUGGUAGGAUACGUAACACACCCCUUCAAAACUUUUAAAAAAUACAUUUAGCACAUGUGCUAUGAAAGCAUACGUACAAAGAGAAAGGGGAAAGUGAUUUAUAAUUCCUACAACAGAGGCCAAGAAAUAGAUUAAAAUAUUUUCAAGACCCCAAAAUAAUGUAUUAUGGUUGGGAAGUCAGUAGAACACUGGAAUAGGUGAAGACCUGACAGUAAUUUUUGUCUUAAGAAUGCUUUCUUUAGGACAGACCCUUUAACCUCACCUCUGUGCAUCUGUUUUUAAAAUGAUUAUAUUUGCCUCUGAUAUUUGAAAGCACUUUUGUAGUUUUGAUGAUGAAAAAUAUAUUAAACGUGCAUAUUACCAUUAUUUAGGAAAUAAUUCCUUAUAUACUGUGAUAAAUCAUUGCUGUUACAUACAGUAACAUGCCUUAAUUACAUUUAAUGCCUUACUGCUUUAUGUAAGUAAAUCCAAGUUUCAGAAUUAAAAAUAAGCAUUAUUUCAUAUGGUCCAAUCAGAUUCGUUACAUAGGCUAUAUAAAUUUGUCUCCAUUUUCACCAUCAAGCACAAAUAAUUGGGUCAAAACUGCCUUUGAGGUCUGUUGAAGAAAAUGGUUCAUUAAGCAAAAAAGAGUAGAGGUAUUUUAUAUUAGCAGUAACAGACAAAUUAUUUAGUAAUCCCUUAACCUCUGUUUUUCAAAGAGAAAAUAUCCAAUUUAGACUUUUUUCCUGAUCUCUAUAUAUAGCAUCAAAUUGGGAAACAAAGGCCAAAGGUGUAUAGAUUGCUUGAAAGGGGGUGGUAGUGCCUCUUUUUAAGAUCUGUUGAGUCGGCUACAGUCUGGCUAAGUAAGAAGCAUUUGCAUACUGAUUCCAUCAUUUAAUCUUUAAAAGUAUGUGUUUUAAAAAUGUAACCAGAAUGAUUCUUCAAUAGAAAUGAGAUUUGGUGGAGUCUGGAUUGCCUGUUUUGUAUAUAAUAUAUACUUAAGAUAUAUAAUACCACCUCAUUUUCUGGGCAUUAUUUCCUAAUUGUUGAUGUUUCAGGCUUUUGAUAAGUCAUUUUAUAUAUUUCAAAUUUAACUCAGAAUAAGUAAAUAUUUAUGGCAAAUGCAGUUUUAUGUACUUUCAGGAGAAGACCAUCAGGAAAAGACAGGACAAAGAAGUCAAACAUUAAAGCCCUUGCAAAUAUUAGAGGACCUUAGACAAUUACCAAAAAGUGUUUAAUAGGGAAGUUGCAAAUGAUUCUCUUAGUAAAUUAAACAUUUAAAAAGUAGUUUUAAUGUGCCUUGGGCAUCUUGAAAAGAAGAGUGUGAUAUAAUUUAUGCUUAGUGUUAACUGGUCAUUUUACAUUGUAUUUAUUAAGUCUGCUGAAAAAUGAGGUUUUAAGGAAGAAAAUGCAGAUUAUUUUAGGGUAAACAGGCCAGGUGUCCUUUGAAGAACUUUGUUUACAUCAAAUUGAUGAAAUUACAGUCAGUGAUUCCUUACUUUUUUUGCUAGUUGUACUUUGAAAUUGUUAUGGGUUCGAUUUCCAAAAUAUGUAACUUAUUUUUUAAAGGAAUAAGGUGUGCUGUGUAUUUGUUGAUUAAAAAUCAUUUGUCUUGCAGAGUAUCCUUUUUUGAAGGAAAUAUACAUCCUUAUAACACAUCAGGUAGUUUUCUUUUUUCUGUAUUUAAAUUAUAUAUUUGAAUUAAUUGAAUAUAAUUUGAGUUACAUAUAAUUCUAUAUAAAGGUUACAUAUUGAAUUAUGGUUCUAAUCUGUUUAGGAAAGAAAUGAAUUUUCUAAGCAUUUAAUACAUUUGGAAUAAUUUUAGUUUCUAAAAAGUACUAAUGUAAGUUAAGUUUAUAUCAAAUGCAAAUUACCUUGUAUAACUAACAAGCACAGUUAUUGUUUAACAUUAUGGAUUUUAAUUGUGUUGACACCCUUCUUUGAAUUUGUUGCUUUACAUGUGUGUCUGUGUGUGUGUCUGCAUGUGUGCACGCAUGUACUUGUAUGCAAUGUAAAAGUAACAGCAGAAUCAUUGCAUUUGGUUUACUUAAAAUUUUGGAGUUAGCAAGUAAACAAAAAGCUGAUAGUUUUAUGAAGUCUCGGUUAAAAUAAAAUUUCUUUGCUAUCUCACUCCUAGGAAGUUAUGGAGUUCAUAUUUUCAAAAGAUAUGUUAAAAAUGGUUACACACUCUGCUGGCCACAUUAAAAAUUAGAAGACUCAUGUUAAAUUAUCUCCUCCAAAGGACUUUUUAUUUACAGCUUUUCUUUUCCUGGACUCUACCUGCUUGGUUCAGUGUCCUGAAGAGUUAUUUAAAUGAACCACUACUUAGUAAUUAGUUCUUUUUUAAAGUAUCUACUUCUAAAAUUACCUAGUUGAAAAUAUGAAGGAUAUGCUUAGUUUUAGAAAUAUCAUGAAGCAAGGAUCUAGUCAGUGUUACAGGGUAAAGGUGGAGUUUUUUAAAGUCUGUAUUUAAAUGGUGCACUGAUGGAUUCAUUUUUAAUUUGCAUUACAAAAAUGUUGCUCAGGUAAUCAGUAUUUUCUUCCACGUAUGUGCAUAUUGCACUGUUAGAUCAUAGAAAUAUCUGAAUGCUUUAAUUUUUAUGUAUGCAAAAUCUAUAAAUCUUUUGUAUAAUGUAUUUUAUACAAAUGUAACUGUAGAACAUUGUUAGCAUGUGUAUCUGUAAAACCAGUUUUUAAAAUUUUUUGCCCCUUAUUUUUCAUAUUUUGAAAGAUCUCCAACAUGUAAUAAAGUUUCUCUUAUUCAAUCUAAAA